ACAGUUGCGGCGGGAGAGCGGCGGGGCCGAGAGCGUGACUCGCCCGCUCCGCGCUGCUUCCCCCGCGCCGCCUCCCCGCGCCGCUCGCGCAGCCAUGUCCGAGGAGAAGCCCAAGGAGGGUGUGAAGACAGAGAAUGACCACAUCAACCUGAAGGUGGCCGGGCAGGACGGCUCCGUGGUGCAGUUCAAGAUCAAGAGGCACACGCCGCUGAGCAAGCUGAUGAAGGCCUACUGCGAGAGGCAGGUGCGGCACCUUGCUCCCCCGCAGAGCCUCCCCGUGUGCGCACUGGUCCUGUGCGUUCCAGGCAUCCCCAGAGCACGAGCGUCUCGGGGCUGGACCCAGAUGCAGCUGCCCGAGGGCUUGUCAAUGAGGCAGAUCAGAUUCAGGUUCGACGGGCAGCCAAUCAAUGAAACUGACACUCCAGCACAGCUGGAGAUGGAGGACGAGGACACCAUCGACGUGUUCCAGCAGCAGACGGGAGGUGUGCCGGAGAGCAGCCUGGCAGGGCACAGUUUCUAGAGGGCCCGUCCCCAGCCCGGGCCGUCCAUCCUCGCAUUGCUGUUGAAUGGUGAGCACGUGACCAUGCCGACCACAAAGGUGUCUGCGGAAACUCGAGGACAUUCACCACGAUGAUUUUCCUCUCUUUGAUGUACUUCAAGUGCAACUCAAAACUAUAUCUGCAGGGAUGAAUCUGUAACUUAAAUUGGGCCAAUCAGAAUUGUUAUCUUUGUUCAGGUAAAAUGAGUUGCAAGAUAUUGUGGGUACUUUUGUGUGCUCAUUUGUGUUUUCCCCCCCUCCUACAACAUUUUUUUAACCCCAAAAUUAUAGCCUGAAUGUUCGCUUUUAGUCUGGCCAGGGAUCUGACUCCUGAGUUGGUUGCCUCUCCCCUGCUCACUCCAGUCACAUAGAGAAUUGGUGUUUCCCGCAGUGGGGAUGCAGCUGUUGGACAGGUAUUGGGGGCAAGGUUGGUAGGGAGGACAGACUGUCACUUGCUGUUACAGGCACAGGUGAUUAAAAUGCUAAAUAUUGCAAAUUUAAGCUUUGUCAGUAUAUGGAAAAGUUGAAGGGAAAAUACUGGAAUGCUUCUUCAAAGGUUAAAAAAUAACCGAGUCUUUUGGUAAUUUGACCCCACGUGCUCUCUGGCCCUCAAGCAUGUAACCUCGGGGUCUGAGGCCCAGGACCCACCCCCCUGCCACCCCUCCCACCCCACUCCCUGCUCAGUACCUGGCGUUGGUACACAGGCAAGGAUUGGCACAACCAAAAUUGGCCUUUUUCUCCCUCUUAAUAUUGAAGAAAUUCCCACAUUUCUCAUUUGGUAAUGGUGUUGUGGCCUCAGAUUUCUUCUAGUAUUUGCUUCUGAUGAAUGAUUAUGGUCUAUACAUAAAAAAGUAAGACUAAGUAUUGCUGAAUUUGCAGUUAUGUUGUCGUGUAUAAGAGCUACUUCCAAGUGUGGUUACAAAUGAACCCAUGGAAUGAUGACUUCAUGUUCUUCUCGUGGGUUUGUGCCGUGCUGCUUUCCAAAUAGGUAUUGAAUUUAUGCAUUAGUCUGGUGAUUUCAGUUCUGUGAAAUAUUUUGGGAUCUAUACCAAUUAAACAUUUUCAUAGUUCUGCCUAUUGUCCUUCCCUGAGGCUCCAUUGCUGCUUGGUGGCCAUUCUCUGCCUUUUUACAGUCACCUGAACAAUGACCCAUCAUCUCUUGCUUGCUUGAAAUCUUGCUGAAAUGUUCUCAUUUCCUGUUUGCUGUAUGGGCUCGGGUGGGAUGUUUGUUGGCUCUGUUGUGUUUAUUCACCAAUUUGUACAUUAUUUGUUGUCCUUUACUACUGUAAACAGUAAAUAUAGUUUGGUAUUCUGUC